AGUGUCCCGAGAGGCGCCGCUUCUUCCGCUUUCUCGUCAGGCUCCUGCGCCCCAGGCAUGAACCAAGGUUUCUGAACUACUGGGCGGGAGCCAACGUCUCUUCUUUCUCCCGCUCUGGCGGAGGCUUUGUCGCUGCGGGCUGGGCCCCAGGGUGUCCCCCAUGGCGGGGCCGCGGGUGGAGGUCGAUGGCAGCAUCAUGGAAGGGGGCGGCCAGAUCCUGAGAGUCUCUACGGCCUUGAGCUGUCUCCUAGGCCUCCCCUUGCGGGUGCAGAAGAUCCGAGCCGGCCGGAGCACGCCAGGCCUGAGUUCUGGAGGCUGGAAGUCCAAGAUCAAGGUCCUGACAAGGCCUCAACAUUUAUCUGGACUGGAAAUGAUUCGAGAUUUGUGUGAUGGGCAACUGGAGGGGGCAGAAAUUGGCUCAACAGAAAUAACCUUUACACCAGAGAAGAUCAAAGGUGGAAUCCACACAGCAGAUACCAAGACAGCAGGGAGUGUGUGCCUCUUGAUGCAGGUCUCAAUGCCGUGUGUUCUCUUUGCUGCUUCUCCAUCAGAACUUCAUUUGAAAGGUGGAACUAAUGCUGAAAUGGCACCACAGAUCGAUUAUACAGUGAUGGUCUUCAAGCCAAUUGUUGAAAAAUUUGGUUUCAUAUUUAAUUGUGACAUUAAAACAAGGGGAUAUUACCCAAAAGGGGGUGGUGAAGUGAUUGUUCGAAUGUCACCAGUUAAACAAUUGAACCCUAUAAAUUUAACUGAGCGUGGCUGUGUGACUAAGAUAUAUGGAAGAGCUUUCGUUGCUGGUGUUUUGCCAUUUAAAGUAGCAAAAGAUAUGGCAGCGGCAGCAGUUAGAUGCAUCAGAAAGGAGAUCCGGGAUUUGUAUGUUAACAUCCAGCCUGUUCAAGAACCUAAAGACCAAGCAUUUGGCAAUGGAAAUGGAAUAAUAAUUAUUGCUGAGACCUCCACUGGCUGUUUGUUUGCUGGAUCAUCGCUUGGUAAACGAGGUGUAAAUGCAGACAAAGUUGGAAUUGAAGCUGCCGAAAUGCUAUUAGCAAAUCUUAGACAUGGUGGUACUGUGGAUGAGUAUCUGCAAGACCAGCUGAUUGUUUUCAUGGCAUUAGCCAAUGGAGUUUCCAGAAUAAAAACAGGACCAGUUACACUCCAUACGCAAACCGCGAUACAUUUUGCUGAACAAAUAGCAAAGGCUAAAUUUAUUGUGAAGAAAUCAGAAGAUGAAGAAGACGCCGCUAAAGAUACUUAUAUUAUUGAAUGCCAAGGAAUUGGGAUGACAAAUCCAAAUCUAUAGAGUAUUUGCCUCUUAAAUGAUACCUCAUUGAUAUAUUGCACUAUUUCAUAAAUACUAUAAAAUAAUGACUAGGAAGUAACUUAUUAAAGGCUAUGACUUAAAUUUGAAGAUGAAGUACAGUGUUCUAGGUUUGCUGAGAAGGCUUCAUUAAAUUAAUCUCACUUUGAAUAUCUCCUGAGAGAUGGACAAUGAAAUAUCAGUUGGUGGAUAUGUGUGAUAGCUGAUUUCAAUAUUGAAGUAUUGAAAUAAAAUAUUCUUUACACCUGAAGUAAAUACAUUUUUCUUUUUUAUGUAAUUAAUUAAAUCAGGGAUAUAGAUUUGAUCUGUAAUUUGGGUAUAAUUCUAAUCUUUGCUGAAAUCACAUCUCAAGUAUAAUGAGGCAACUUUAUGCAAAUGUACUUGUUGUGACAACAAUAACAUUUUCCUUUUUUUUUUUUUUUUUUGAGACAGUCUCGUUCUGUCACCCAGGCUGGGGUGCUGUGGUGUGAUCUUGGCUCACUGCAACCUCUGCCUCCCGGGUUCAAGCAAUUCUACUGCCUCAGCUUCCUGAGUAGUUGGUAUUACACCACCAUGCCCAGCUAAUUUUUGUAUUUUUAGUAGAGACAGGGUUUCACCAUAUUGGUCAGGCUGGUUUCGAACUCCUGACCUCGUGAUCUGCCCGCCUCGGCCUCCCAAAGUGGUGGGAUUACAGGCGUGAGCCAGUGCACCCGGCAACAAUAACAUUUAAUAGGCAUUGUCUCAUUCUAAUGAUAUAUACCUUCUACCUAGUGGGCACUUUGUACAUAUUUAUUUUUUAUUUUAUUUAUUCAUUUUUUUUGAGACAGAGUCUCACUCUGUCACCAAGUUGGAGUGCAGUGGCACAAUCUCAGCUCACUGCAACCUCCGCCUUCCAGGUUGAAGUGAUUCUCCAGCCUCAGCCUCCCGAGUAGCUGGGACUCCAGGCACGUACCACCAUACCCAGAUAAUUUUUGCAUUUUUAGUAGAGACGGGGUUUCACCAUGUUGGCUAGGAUGGUCUCCAUCUCCUGACCUCGUGAUCCGCCCACCUUGGCCUCCCAAAGUGCUGGGAUUACAGGCAUGAGCCACCACAGCUGGUCGUAAAUAUUUUUUGAAUUUGAAUCUGUUUUGGAAGCCAAAUAUGUUUUGGAAGCCAAACAAUUAAGAGAAGUAAAAUUUUAACCCUAGUAGGUUUCGCAGAUUCAUCCCCAGAUAUGUUUUUGUUUGGCUUGUGUUAUUAACAAAUAAAUGAGUGUCUUUCAAAUGGAA